GUGUUCUUACCACAUAUAUCCUUUAGAGUUCAUCUUAUCAUUCCUAAGGGGGUGUUCAAGAAGAGAAAGAAUGAUCACUGGUGUUCUUAAAUCCAAACAUUCACCUUACUCUCGACUUCCUCCUUUUAAAACUACCUAUAGAGCAUCUUCAUGUUAAUUUGUUACAGAUGGCUCAAACUCAACAUCUCCAAAUGAUUUUCUCCCCUGCCCCUCUGCCUCCUUGGAUCUGUUCUUCCCCCUGUGCUGCCUAGCACUUUGACGAUGCCCACUAUCAACCCAGUCCUCUAAAUUAGAAGCUUGGAUGUUAUCUUCAGCUUCUCCAUUUCUCUAAUUCCUCAUCACGUCGUUAACUGAAUCCCGUGAAUUCCAUUUUCUGAAUGUCUUGCAAAUUCAUUCCUCACUGCCACUGUAUUAGUUCAGCCUCUCAUCAUCUCACUCUUGGAACACGUGUUCUUUCUCAUUCUCCUAACUGUUGCAAGUAAAAUCGCGUCACUUCCUUGAAUAAAAUCAUUAACUGGUUUCUCACUUUAAACAACAUAAAUUAAAAUUCCUUAGCACAGCAUGCAAGAUCAUUUUCUGGCUCUUGAGAGCCCCAUCUCUUGCCAUGUCUUUUUAGUGCUCUAUGCUCAACCGUUCUGUGUUACCUGCAGUAUACCAAAUAGGUAAUAAUGUUUCACUUCUCCGCACUUAUCCAUAUACUCUUUCCCUUUUCCUGGAAACUCAUCCUUCCCUUGUCUUGCCUUUAAGGGUCUUAUUAAUCCUUCAAAUUCAGCCAAAAAAUUAUUUCCCAGCAGAAGAAUCUUUUCCUACCACAUAGCAGACAGUUUACAGAAUUGUUUUGAAGAUUAACUGAGAUAGUAUAUAUGAAAAUACUUAACUAGGAAGCUCUAUUUAAACAUAAGAUACUAUAUAAUGACAAUACAUCUAUUAAUUAUUAAAUAAAAGCCAAAGUCUGCUUUUCAUUUCAAAAGGCAAAAUGAAUGCUACGUUGAUAUGAGAAAAAACUCUCGAAUCAUUUUGAUUGAAUUUAAGGUUCUUUGAUAUGAAGAAACUUUAUAACUUUUAAGCAUGAGUGUCUUCCACCUUGAUUAAAUUAUUAUCAUGCAAAUAAUCCACAAAGUAUUUAAAAGCAUUUAUUAACUGAUUUUUCAAGGACUUUUACUCAAUUAUUCUUGUUUGUUUAUUUUUCUGGACAUUAGGCAUAAAUUACAAGUGUAGAACUAUAUUAAAGUAUCUUCUGUUUUAUAGCUUUUAAAUGAUUUUACUAUUCUUAUGUUAUUUGAUUCACAAACAGAGAGCAUUACCCCCAUUUCAUAGGUGAGAUCAACUCCUUAGGAAGGCCAUAUUACUGAACAUUAUGAACUUGAUUAAAAAAAAAAGAAGAAGAAGAGAAAGGCCAUAUUGUAAUGCUUUCUAAAAGUAAAGUGGUAUAAUGUGACAAAACUAGGUAGGGGCAACCCAGUAAUGUAAUACUAGUUAUUCAGCAACUGCUACUCUCCGAUGCUGAAAAAAAAUGAGCUACUAGUUUCUAUCUUUCCGAGUUUCAGGUUCUUGCUUGGGAUGACAAGAAUAUGCAGUAAUAGAUUAUAAUUUAGGAAGAAGAUGAAUUACCAUUACAUACACUACUAGAAGAGAAAACCAAAAAUAUUUGGCUCACUUUGUUUUUCUUGAUUAGGAAACCAGAGUAUAUAAAAACAAAAAGUCAAAGAGUAUUGGGUAUUCCACUAAUAGUUCAUAGUCUAAAAUACCAUGGAAAAUUUUGCACUAAAAUUAAAAAUUAUAUACUUACUAAAGCAUUUUUAAAAUUUAUACAUUUUGCCUCAAAACUCAGAGGCAUCAAGGAAUUCAUUUUUAUUCAAGUUGCUUGAAAUAUAACAAAGAAGGAAGAAAUUCUAUUGGAAAAUCCUAUGGAGUAAUAGUUCUGAGGCUAUCUACUCAUAUUUGGUGAUAGAGAUGUAGUUUACUGUGUCAUUUCAGACUGGUUUGUUGUAUUUUUGAUUUUAAUGAAAGAAAAUUAAAACGAAAUCAGUAAAACAUCAUCCAGAUGGCUGGAGUGCAAUGGUACAAUCAUAGCUCACUGCAGCCUCAAACUUCUGGCCUCAAGUGAUCCUCCUGCUUCAGCCUCCCAAGUAGCUAGCACUACAGGCAUGCACCCCUAUGCCUAACUAAUUUUUUAAAUUUUUUGUAGAGAUGGAAUCUGGCCAGGUUGACCAGGUUAUUCUUGAACUCCUGGCCUCAAGCAAUCCUCCUGCUUUCACCUCCCAGUGUGCUUGGAUUACACAUAUAUGAUUUUAUUUGAAAACAAAAUUUCACUGCUAAUUUUUAAUGUUUAAAUCACGGAGGGACUAGAAGAGUCAUAACUAGAGGUAAAGAGAAUUGGAAGAAAAGUUUUUACAAUCACAUUAGAAGAAAUAAACACUUGAACCAGAAAAGUGGCAGUGGAAAUGGAAAGUGUAUGAAUUUGAUAUUGUUAGAGUAGAAUCAACAAAAUUUGAUACUUGAUUAUGUAUAUUGGAGAAGGUAAAGUCAAAUGCAAUCAUAAGAUUUGGAACUGGAUCAUUGGGACAAUGGUAUUGAUUUUAGUAAAAACAGAAAUGCAAGUUUGGAGAAGAGGAGAGCAAGAGGAUUGACUUAACUGCUGGACAUGUUUCUUGCAUUUGAAAGGCUAUUGGCACAUAUAGGUGGAGAGGUCCAGCAGACAUCAAGAAAUUGCAGGGAUGGAACUUGGGUGGGAAGUCUGUGCUAGAAAUAUAGAAUUGGUGGUUAUUCAUGUACAGGUAAUGGCUGUAGCCAGAGAAUAGGUUUGAUUGACAAAGGAGGAGUAUAAAGAGAAGAGACAAGAAGAGUAAAACUUAACCACCAAAGUUUAGAAAAAAGGAAUUUGGAAGAGUUGCUUUUGCACUUGUUAUUCUCCCUACAUAUUUGUUUGCAAAUUCCUAGAAAGUAGUAACAGUUUUACUGAUUUUAGUAUUGUCAAACAGCACUUGGAAUAUUGUCUGUAAGAAAGUAUUUGCAGGAUUAAAAUGACGAUGUGUAUUUAACCCAGCUAAAGUAGAACAUGGUCUGUUAAUAACAAAAAUAAUAAUUUGUUUCAAAUAUAUGCAUGCUGGCUAAAUUGUUUUAGAAAAAUGUUAAUAUUUAAUUAACUUGAUUAAUAACUUUUCAUAUGCACAUGCAUGCAUAUGAACAUAUAUGUGUUUAUCAUCUAUCUAUCUAUCCAUCUAUCUAUCUAGUUUUUUGUUUUCAUAUUUGGAGUCUGUAGUAGAUAUUUUUGGAGGAGUAUGCCUAGCCCACAAGUCAAUGGUUCCCUUGCCUCCAAAAGGGUCUAAAGAAACAGGUUCCUGACUGCUGUUUGUUCUGGACACUAAAACCUCGCUAGACCAAUUGGAUUUUUUUCUUAUAAUUUUUUUUUCUUUUUUGAGGUGGGGGUCUCGUUAUGUUGCCCAGGCUAGUCUCAAACUCAUACAAAAUUCCUGAUAUCCUUAUAAGAGAAAAAACACAGACACAGAAAGACACAGGCAGGGAGAAUGCUGCGUGACUACAGGGGCAAAGAUUGGAAUUAUGCACAAGCCAGAGAACACCAGAGAUUUCCAGCAACAACAAGAAGCUAGAAGUGGCAUGGAACAGAUUCUCUCUCAGAACCCCCUAAAGAAAUCUCCUGAUGAUACUUUGAUUUUAGAUUUCCAGCCCCCAGAACUGUGGGAGAAUACAUUUUUGUUGUUUUAAGCUUCCAAGACUGUGGUAUUUGUUACAGCAGCCCUAGGAAACUGGUGUAGAGGACAACUGCAUUUAAAUACAGCAUGUGGGUGUUAGGUUUAUGAUAAAGAAUAUUCUGGCAGUGCGAUAAUAGAAAGAGUUUUCUUUUCUGCAAAUAUGCUUCCCCCCCCACCCCGGCUUUUUUUACUGUGAAAAUUGCCGAGGUUUGAAUUAAGAGAUGUGGAUUCAAAAACCAACUCUGCUUCUUAUUAGAUGUGGUCUUGGGCAAAUUACUUAAGUUCCCUUCAUGCCCUGAUUUCCUUAUUUAUAAAUUGGGAAAGAAUAAAAAGUAGAGAUCUAUGGUUCACAAAUUCAAGAUAUUGGGCAUCUAAGAAAUUCUGGAUAAUAAGUUAAUAGUGCUAAUUUGCAUCUAAGAUGAUAUUGAGCCAGUUUCUUCCAAUGCAAAGCUAAAUUAAAUUCACAGUUUUAGUUUUAUUUAAAAUAACUUCCUUAGAGACCUUUCAUUAUUGUUGCUCAUGGAAAUCGGAUUAGGUAUACUGAUCACAGUACCACUGCUGGAAGUAAUUCAAAUUCUGCUUAAGAUUUGCUAGGCUAGUUUAUGGAUAUUUGAAUAAAAUUCAGUAUUAAUAGCACUGUAAUGUUAAACAAUAUUCUGAAAUUAGACUUAUAUAACACCUUGCCAAUGAUCCAUAUAAUGUCAUUUUUAAUAGACUAUUUUUUAGAGCAGGUUUAGGUUCACAGCACAUAUGAUGUUUUUAGAAACAUUCAUUGACUGAAUUCUGGUUGUGUAGAUUGUAGUACAGUAUUAGAAGUUCAAACAUGUUGAUUGUGGAUUGGUUGAAAAAUAAGACUAAAUAACAUUAUUUAAUAUGUUAUAUAUCUUAAUAUUCAUAAGGGACAUGUCCUAAGGCUUUCCCGACUCCCCAGUAUGUGAAUAUUACUCUAGGAAAAAAUUACUUUGUUGGUAAAUGGCCAUAUUAUUGCCUAUGAGUAUAAAAUGAGAUGAUAAAUAACAACAGCAAAGCUACAUUCAGCUGCACAUACCACAUGAUCAGCUGACUAAACUUACUAAUUUAAUUAACUGCAAGCAACAGCUUUAUAGUUCCAUAAAAUUCACAUUUGUGCUUUAGCAAAAUGACAUAUUACUACCUGUCAUGAUAACCUUCAGGGUCAUUUACAAAUAGAUACAGCCCAAAGAUUAAAUCUGUAAUGGUUACAUUCUAUGAAAAUCCUGCUACCUGAAAACUUUAUGAAAAUUUUCAUACAUCAUUGUACAAUUUGAAAAAUAAGUAGUUGAAACUUGAGAGCAUGAGCAUUUUGAAAGCAGUUUGAAUCUGAUGGAUUAAGGACCAUUUUAAAUGAACUAAAAUUUACUCUUUGGUUUUUAUGCCUUCAACACUCACUUUUAAAAAUAGGCCUUUAUUAAGACUUCUAAAUAGAUUGAAGUUCUUUCUCCCGUUAUUGAAGAUAACAGAUCUAUCAAUCUAAGAGAAUGGACCAUUAAUAUUAUUAUUUAUGCUUGUAUUAUUUUUAUCUUAAAAGAUAUGUGGAUAAUUUCCCACUUUGGUCUAGAGGAAAGAAUACAGUAACUCAAUAUAUGUCUUUUUUUUUUUUUUUUUUUUUUUUUUUUUUUGAGACAGGGCCUGACUCUAUUUCCCAGGCUGGAUCCAGUGCAGUGGCACAAUCUUGGCUCAAAGCAGCCUCAACCUCUUGGGCUCAAGUAAUCUUCCCACCUCAGCCUCCCGAAUAGCUGGGACCACAGGCAUGCGCCACCACACCUGGCUAAUCUGUUUAUGUCUUUAGGGACACCAGUAUUCAUCUGAGGAGUCAGUGCCUCUCGAAAGCUGCCAAAAUAACUUGUAGGAUCAUUUAAAAACUAAUUACAGAAAGCUUUACCCAGGAACAUUAAGGGAGUUAAGAUAAAAUGUUCCUGAUGCUGUCAGGUGAGUGUGCUUUUUAUUUCCUUCUCUGAAUAUUUCUUUUUGGUCCCUGCUAUAGCAAGGCUUAUGCUGUUACUUGGUGACACAUUUUAUUCAAAUAGUAUGAAUAAGCGGAAAGGUGCCAAAGAUGAAUCUCCUGAGAUUUAUGAUAGAAUCUUCUCCAGAGAGAAGAGAAUUUUACUCUUUGGUAGUUAUGGUGACACUCUUGUUCUGUGAGAAGAACUGGGAAUGGGGCAAGAAACAGGCAGUAUCAGUCAGUGAUUUCUGAUCAGAUCCUAUGCCUGAAGUUAGAUGAAUCUGAGCAGGGCAAGAUCCUCUGAAAGAUCUGACUCACUAAGAGCAUGUCCAGACAAAAGUGAUCCCCCAACCUGUAGUUUAUAGUGUUCCUAGAGCUCCACUCAAAUUUGUACCCCCAAAGGACGAAUUGUACAAUGGAAUUCCACAGGAAGAUUCAGAUUACAAUGUGAUGCUUAAUUUGUAUAACUGUGAAUUUUCUACUUAUUCUUUAAGGUCUUGUUUAAAUCCCAUGAAUACUUCCCUGCUAAUCUAUCCCAGGGUGAUAUUUUCUUCAUUUCAAUUUUUAGUAGUCUUAAUAUGAAUGGAAUAUUCAAUGAAAUAUCACCAGGACACAUAGUUCUUCUUUUAGAUUUUAGUAUCUAAUGAUAUCAUAAAGCUACUUAUUGCAGAAGCUGCAUCUUAUAUAUUUACUUUGUAUCAUUCAGAAUGCUAAGUUCCUGAUUCAUAAUAGAGCUCAACAUUAUUUGGUUGAUUAAUUACUCUUUCUUUUUAGCUUUCAUUCUCAGUGGGUUAUUUUUCUAUGAUUUUACUAUCUAGAAGAAUUAACAUUCCAUUGGAAAUUUUGAUAAUUGGGAAGAUUAUUUUUAUAACUUGAUAAUUUUAUUUAUAAUUCAUACUAUGAUACAUAAUUCUGCACUUACAGAACCAAAAACAGUAGAAAACAGUUGUUUUUUAGUAAUUCUAAAGAGAAAAAAAAUUUUAAGUAAUUUAUUUAUUUAUUUUUUAUUAUUAGUUGACAAAUUAUGAAUGUGAUGUUAUAGUAAAUGUAUACAGAGGAAAGUUGACAUGUCCCAACAAGUGAUUAUAUUUCUUAAUAUAUAAGAUAUUUUAUAAUAUGUUAGAAUAUACUAUGAAAGUAUUUAAGAAAAAGUGACUGUGUGUUUAAGUUAAUUUUCAUGAAUAUAACAUGAUUAGAUUGAUGAAAGAAAACACAUAAGACUUGACAGGGAAUUUCUAGAUUUGUAUGACUGGGAACAGUUUUUACAAUUGGCAACAGACACUGGAACCAUCUUUUGGCAACUAGUAUAAUCAUUUGAAAGCCAAGAAAUAUGUUUAUAUUCUUUCUUAGGUACUGGUCCUCCUUUUUUGCUACUGACAAAUGAAGUUUGUGCUAGACUUUAUUUUAUUUUAUUCUUUGAGACAUGGAAUUGUUCUGUUGCCCAGGCUGGGGAGCAGUGGUACAAUCACGGCUCACUACAUCCUCCGACCUCUCCCGGCCCAAGCAAUCCUCCCCUUCAGCCUCCUGAGUAGCUAGGACCACAGCUGCGUGCCACCAUGCCAGGCUAAUUUUUAAAAUUUUUUGUAGAGAUGGGUGUUCCUAUGUUGCUCAGGCUGGUCGUGAACUCCUGGCCUCAAGUGAUCCUCCUUCCUUGACUUCCCAAAGUACUGGUAUUAGAGGCGUGAACCACCGUGCCUAUCUGACUUUAUUUUUUCUCUAACUGUUCAUUAGGUAGCUUCCCUGAAACUGAUCAUAGCUUUCCAAGGUCGUGGUAAAAAUUUAAAUAGUUUUUCCCUCUCAUUCUUUUUAAGGAAAAUGCCAUAUAUAUUUUUAUGUUUUAAGAGUGAUUGUCUAUAUGCAGAUAAUAUUAAAAUCUACAUGCUACUGAUUUAAUGAUUAUUUGUCGCCUACCCAUACUUAAACUAAUUUUUGUGAAAUUAGUUCCAAAAAUCACAAAAUAAACACUUACCAUAUUAAUCAAUCAAUAAAAUAUCUUCAAGGAGUUUCUGAUUAAAAGUAUUUAGAUGACAACAAACCUGAGUAAAAAUUUUGCCACCUUGCAAUAUAGUCAAAAUGAGACUACAUUAAAGCAGGGAUCAAAAUUUGAAAUCAUUUUUUAAAACCAAGCCAACCACACUAGUAGAAAGAGGUAAGAGGUUUAUUUUUCAUCAAGUGUUAAGAGGUUUCUAUCCUCACAAAGAAUUUAUAGGUAUCAUCUGAUAGUAUAUAUAAGUAGAACAGAGUAUAAAUUAUAUCAUUUUUCCCAUGAUGAUAUAUAGUUAGAACAAUAUUAAUAGUGGCAAAAAGAAGCUGGGAGAAUGCAGUUCUGAUGUUUCUGCCCUUCAUAACCAUGCCAAAUCAUUUUAAUAUGCAUAUGAACAUGAAAUCAUCUGCAUUUAUAAUCCUUAUCUGCUGUUGAACUCCAUUUAUGCUUUUCCAACUAGCAGUCUAGAGCAAUAGCACUUUCUUCAAUACAAUAUGUUUAAAUUCAGAUGCCUCACCCUCAUCCUUAUGAUAUACUUUCACACAAGUUCAACCUCUCUACUCCCCUCUGCCAUUAAUAAUAUGUUUAUUUUUCUAGUCAACUGGGCUUGAAACCUUGAAAUAAUCACUGAUUUCUUACCCUCAAAGCAGCUGUAACAAAGUUCUAAUGAUUAUUUCUAAAAUAUAUUAUUCCUGUGGCCGAUACUACAAUACAGGUUCUUAACAUUUCUGGUUAUAUUAUUUCAAUGUCUUCUAAACUAGACCAAUUUCUCCUAGAGACAGUAUUCUCUUGCUUCUGGUUCAUGCUAAAUUGGCUACUAUAUAAAUUUUUCUAAAAUGCUAUUUACAUAUAUCAUUUUCCUGAAACACACAAAUAUUGUCUUGUCUGUGGCAUAAAGUCCACCUUUCCUUAGCUUUGGCAUGCAAGGUUCUGAACACCCUGGCCUCAGCCUCUUUCCCUCCUCUCAUCCUUUUUUUCUCUCCAUUCCCUCCCUUCCCUUGUUCCUCCCUUCUUCCUUUCCUCUCUUUUUCUUUCAUUCUAAAAAUAGGAAACACAGACAGAAAAGGAUAUCAUUCAUAAAUGUACAACAUAAUGAAUUAUCACAAAAUGAACACACCACUCAGGUAAAGAAAUAGAAGGCUGAAGCAUGAUAAUUUUCGGGGUGCGGAGCCCAUAUUUCUUAUGUUCUUUACUACUCUAUAUUGGCUGUCAAUAGAUUUCUGGCCUUCUUAAAAUUCUUACUAUGAUUUCAGUGUAAAUUGAUACAAGUUUAUAGUGUUCAUUCCUCAAAGCAACAGAAAAAAAUCAAAAUAAAACAAAAAGCCUGAAUUUUGAGCUUGUUUUCUUGCCAGAGUUUGAAAACCUUUUUCAUUAAAAAAAGUGCAAAAUAGUUUUGUAAUUCUACUGAACCUCUGGCAAAUUCAGUUAAGGCACAUUUUUUGAGCAGUGCAGUGAGUGUAGUUUUGACUGUUGUAUAUCCAAACUCUUAUCCUUUUCUUGUAUGCCUUUCUUGUAGAGGGUUUAGGGUUACAGAAAGGGUUAGUGGUGAAUGAUGCUACAUUUCUGUUUCUUGUCUUCUAUUUCUCAAUCCCCAAUACCAAAGUCUCCUGCAGACAUCUGGGAUACUUCUUUUGGAGUUUAAACUGGCAUAUUUUGGUUCCACAUUGAAGUUCCUGACAAAGUUUGACCUCGUAUUAGUACUUCAACAAUGGAUAAUUAUGGUCUGAGGCACUUCGUCUAUAAAUCAAACUCGGUAGAAGGAGUAUUCCCUGCAAUGACAUGCAGCAAUUGAAAUAGUCAUCUUUUUAUUUUUUGGUAAUUAUUCUACCAGUUUGGAGUGUAAAAGUAGAAAAUAUGAUGCUGCUAUUACAUUGCUAAGCAAGCAGAAGGAUAUCCAACAAGGAACCACAUAUAAAUUUAAGUGUUCAUGACUACAAGCCUAUACCUAUUGAAAGACGAGCCUUGUGUCCAGAACAGUGAUGAGCACAUAUUCUGUGCUAAGUAUCAUUUGAAUGAAUUUUUUUAUAUGUGUUUGCACCCGACAGAGAUUUUAUAUGCAAAAAUAAAAAAAAGAAAAUCCUCUGUCUUUUUAUGCUUUACUUUUUAAAAAAAAUACAACACCUGGAUUGUUGUAGAGCAUAUUAACUUAAAAUUCUAUUUAUAAUCCCUUGAUUCAUUAUAUUACUUAUACAUUACAUAUAUAAUAUAUAAUAUCAUAAUUAGCAUGGCUUGGAAAUAUAUGUUCAUUUUGCUGCUGCUUCUCUUUCUUACCUUUUUGUUUUCCACAUACGAGAAGAAGGGUCAUAUAUGUAUGUUAUCUCUUUACUCCAAUCAUGAUUACUGUGGUUCUGUUCCUGCUUAGCUACACAUUAUAUUCCAAGCCCAGCUGCUGCCUUGUUUGAAUGUUUCUUGAAGAAGGCAUUGUAACUUUAACCAAGCAGCCCGUAUUCUAUAUCUAUGGUUUUCUAGGUUAUUGUCCAAGGUGCAGGCCAGAUAACUUUUAAGAAAGUCAUUUCUAGAGUCCCUCUGAGUGGUCUCCAGAAAUUGUGGGAUUAGCUUGUGGAAGUUGAUAUGAAACUACAGUUAAGUGGGUGAUGAGCAUGAAUGACCUCAGGCAAAAAUUGCAAAGCAACUUUCUUCUCUAUUCAUAAGUACUAUGUAAAACAAAUAUUACAUAUAUAAUGAGUAUGUAUCAGAUUGCAUUUCAAAAUUAAACAUGUUGAUCCUAUUUUUUCCCCAUAUAGGGCAUAAUUAUCUUUGAGAAACUAUUAAAAAUUAGGGAAAAGGUUAUCCUUUAACAGAAUUGUGUGACAGCACAUUGCAGUACGCACUAAUGCCUCUCCCCAAUUCCCAGUGUUACAUUUCCUUGUCUACUUUCUGUGAUUCUUGGCUCUUUUUCUGCUAGACCCCUUCAAAUAUCUGCUCAAGGGUAUCAUGGCCUUGGUCACAUUUUCUUUCAUUAAUUCUCCUCUUAAAAGGUCCACUGAUGCUAAAUUCAGUUAUGUGGAAUAUACCAAACCCAUUCAUUAUAAUUAGAGAAAUCCUGGGAUACAUACUACAUUCAGGAUAGGCAAGUUACUAUAUCAUAAUGUCUAUUUAGAUUUAGUUUUUUAAAAUAUUGCUCAGUGUCUUCCAGGCCCUUGUUGCUUUUCACCCUGAUUGGCCAAGCCUUCUUGUAACCAGAUUCCUUGAGUCAGUGGCUUUCAGAUUAAUUCAUCUUUAUUCCUACCUCUCAGUUUAAUGUUAGAGCUAUUUCCCCACUUUCUUUGUCUCUGACAAAACAGAGCUCUAUUUUUUGGACCUUAGGUUAAAUUUUGUUUCUGGUUGAAACUACUCUCCUGAGGCUUCCUAGAUCCUGUUUUACAGGAAUUUUUCAAUCCUUUCCUCUGUGAAGCCUUCCUUGCCUAUUUUGUAUAGAAUUUAUGUAAUCCCUCCCCGAAUUUUCACAGCAUUUAUUUUUUACAGUACUUAUUUUCUAUAUCAUUCACUUGGUAUAUUUUCAAGCUGACAGUUUAAAAAAUGUCUAUCAUAUGGUAGGUCCCAUGCUAAAUAUUGGAAAUAUGAAGAUAACCAAAUUAACUAUCCCAAGUCUUAAAGAGCUAAUAAUUUAGUGUAAGAGAUAGUAUGUUACAACUAAUCUCUAUAUAAUUUUAUAAGUAUGCAAUAGAUGUCUGAAAUGUUAUGGGAACAUGGAUGAAUAAUUGAUUAGUAUGGAAAUAAAAGGAAGUUUUACAGAAAACUAUAGGCUUAUAGGAAUUAAAUGAAUGAAUAUAACCUUUAAGACUCAGCUUUUGGACACCAUUUCUUCCUGAAAGUCUCCCCUAAGUCUCCAGACUACAUUUGAUCCCCUUUCUUCAGUGGCUAGAUAUAACUUUACUGUAGCGCUUAUCCUAUUAUACUGAAAUAAACUAUAAGUCUGUCUCCCUACUGUACUCUAAAUUUCUGGGAAAAAGACUGUGUAUUAUUUUGGAUUCCUGAUACUUAACGCAAUGCUUGCUGAAUAAUAGAUGCUCAAUAAAUGUCUUUUGAACUGAACAACAAAACAACAAAACACAUGAAUGUUUGGAAAUUGCAAGUAGUUUUGUGUGGCAAAUUGUGAGAGGCACAGGAGAGGAGAGUGAAGUGGCUGAAGAUAAGGCUGAAAAAUAGCUAGGACAAAGUUGUGAACAGCCUGAUUCGGCAAUGUAUUGUUGGUUAUCCUUUUAUAUGCAUAUUUCUUGUUAGAAUGCAUUCUUUAGAGACAAGGAUUAAAUCUUACAUGUCAAAAUAUUUCAUUCAGCAUCAGGCACAGAUCCUUGCACAUAAUAGAUGUUCAGCAAAUCAAAGGAGAGUUAAAUCAUCACAUGACAGCAUCCACUUAAAAGUACUUUGAAGAUUAUAUUAUGAUUCAAUGAUUAUUCAUUGAUAGUAGGCAGUGGCUAUACUCUGUCCUAGAUAAUGAUAGAGGGAGUAUUCUUUUGAUCCAUUGUUUUCCUGUGAACAGAACCUAUGUGCAUUCUGAAAUCACGAAACUAUAAACAAACUUAAAAUAUUAAAUAGCUACUUUUUUGUAUAUGUUAAGUUUUGGACUUUCCACUCAUAAAGAACUAUCAAAUGAGAUGAAAACUAACUACAACGAGCUUCUUUUAUUUUUAAAUGAGGUUUUUGCAUAUGUCCUGGCAUCAAAUAUAGAGUCUAUUGAAUUGCUUGACUUUGAUAUUAGCUAGACAAACUGCCUGGCUCACUACAGCUAUAAGCUUGUAGUAAGAAUUGACUUAGAUAGUAUGAAUAAUAUAAAUUACUAUUGAAACAUAAGACAGAGUUUGAUGCUGUACUAUGCUGGUAACUGUUAACAACUGGUUUUCUAGAAAAAAAAGCUCUGAUCUGUAGCAUAUGCUGAUUUCAGUGAUAUAAAUACUUCCAUUAUGAGCCAUUUACAGUGAUGUAAAUACUUCCAAACUACCCACGUGAAGUUACUGAAAUACACAGUUGGGAAGAGAUGCUAACAAUCAACUCUUCUGAAUCUGUAAGAGCCAGCUCAGCACACUAUGAGUUUGAUAAUAAUUAUUGUAAUUAAAAAUGUUUUUAAAUGGACAUUGACUGGGUGCCCAGGACUCUUCUAAAUGCUUUAUAUACUGUAUUUCAUUUACUUUACCCAGCAAUCUAUGAGGUAGGUUCUAUUUUUUAAUUCCCAUUUAUGGGAAGCUGUGUCUCAGAAAAACUAAAUAAUUUGCUCAUAUUACACAUCAAGGAAUGAGUGGACUAUAGAUUCAAAAACUUAGUUUGAUUCGACUCUACUCCUCCAACUACUAUUCAAUAUUUCUUUCAGGAUAUAAAAUUAAAUUAUGUUCAGCAUAGUUUUCAUGUUAAAUGUAUUUUUUAUUUAAUGUCAAUAUAUGUAAUUCCUUGAAAAUUUUAAGUAAAAGAUAGCUAUAUAAAUUUGCCAUGUCCAACUAAAUAUUUAUGUGACUAAACUCAGGAAAAAACUACAAAAGGAGGAAGUAAUCUAAGUAUUUUAAGUUUAUAUGAUUAAAAAAAGACAUUUUGUCCUCUCAAAACCUUGAAAAGAUUUUUACAAAAGUCUAAUUGGAAAGAACUCGUAAUUGUUUUUAAAAAAGGUGUUAUUUGCAAUUGCACGGAUUCUAAUAAAAAACAAACUCUUGCUUUAUUUCAGCGACAGGGUUCUUAAAUUGUUACUGAAAUUUAUUAGAGUAUCAAAUGGAUGUUGUAAAUAGUGGAACAUUCCACCUGUUUUUCCAAUACUUAGAGCUCAGGAAAAAGGUUAUUUCUAAUUAGCUAAGUAAGCAGAAAAUAUAAUAACAUAAUAAUGCGGAGAAAUUUAGAAGUUAAAAAAAAGGUUAGCAAAUAAAACUGUAGGGGUCUAAAGAUGACUGUAAACUUUGGAUCACUGCAGAAAACUUUCCUAAGUAAGACCUGCCACUAUGCUUUAAGCAAACGAAGCAGCAUAUGGCCUAGACUGAAACUGCGAAGGGCUUUAUACAUUUAAGGGAUGGCAAGAAGUUAAGUGCUGCAGGAAAGUAAGUUGUGUUGUGGGAGUAGAUGUGGAAGCUGAAAAAAACAGUUUAGAACUGAACUAUGAGGAACUUUCUAUGUCAAAUUAAAGUUUGUAUUUUAUUCUGAAGGGCAUCAAAGGUUAAAAGAAGUUCUUAAGAAAGUAACAAAAUGAUUAAUAUUCUAUUAAGAAAAAAACUUUUGUAAUGGUAUUGGGCAGAAGUUGAGAAGAGACUAGUAAAAUGAAGACUGGUUUAUUACAAUAUUCUCAGAAAGAGAUAACGAGAGAUUGAAAUAAAGAUGAUACAUUAUGGAUAAAAGGGGGAUUAAUUUCAGGGUCAUAUUUGAUGUAAAAUCAACAAGAUUUGAUGAAUGUCUAUGUAGGGGAUGCAUUUUGGGAAGUAGUAAAACAAAAAAAGAGAAAAAGUUAAGGAUAAUAUAAGAGUUUUAGUUUAGGAGACUGGAUAGAUUAUGAUGUCAUUAAUGAACAUUGAGGACAAAAAGGUGGUUUAUAGUUUAAAGCAUUUGCACAUAUGUUAUCACAUUUAAGAUGUUAUUUAUGUUACAAAUUACCAUUAUUGCGCUGAUAAAAACUUAAUCUUAUAUGCAAAUAAAUGUACACAGUAUCCUGAUUUUCUUAUUUUCCCCUAGUGCUUAUCAUUGACUUGAUGAAAAGUGCUAUUUGUGUUAUUUAUAGCCAUAUUUAUUUUAAAUAUUUUUAGUAAGUGAUGAUGUUUUCCUUUCUAACUGCUGUAUUUAAAUAUUUUUGUUAGUGGUUCUUUUAACUGUUUGAAAUAUAUUUUAUUAUCUUUCAGUUUGAAACAAACUUUUAGAUUUAGCAUAUUUAUUCACUUCUUACAUGAUUUAUUAAAAGAAGUAAAAGGGAAAAACUGUCUUGUCAUAUUUCUGGUUCUACCAUGAAACACAAAUGAUGCUAAAACCACUAAUAUUUGAAGUCCAUUUUGAACUCCUAUGGUGUUAUAGCUCAGCAUAGUUUUCAUGUUAAAUGUAUUUCAACAUGAUUAUAAAAGCAAGUCUCUAAUGUAUAAAACUAAAGCAAAAUAACACAAAAACAAGAAACUUAAGGCACUUUCAAGACACCAUGAAUCCAUUUGAGUUGGUAAAUGAGUAUUAACCAUGGAGUCAUUUCAUUUCUUCUAAUUAACUGAGGUACUUAGAGGCACUGGGGAUACAAAAAUUAAUAAAUCCUUGUCCUGAUUAAUGGAGCCUAGUGGAGGGGACAUAUAAACAACUCAAUACAAUAAAGACAUUUUAAGUGUUCUACAGUUAGAAAUAAAUUGCUAUAGGAAACAGAUGACGAUGCAAGUAAUUCUGCCCAGGGAUUGGCUACAGCAGGGAGGAGGAAGAGAAGCUUUCACCGUAGAGGUAACUUUUGAGUAGGGCCAUUUAAGGCUUAAUAAGAAUUUGCCAGGAGGAGAAAUGAAGGGCUUUGAGAACAUACAUAAAAGAGCAAGAAAAUAAACAUUCUGGUGUAGGCAGCAUGGGGGCAAAUUGUUUAAAAAAAAAAAAAGAAGCUGAAAGAGUUAAGUAGGACCUAGUAGUGAGGAUGUGACAUACUAUGCUUAAGGACAUUAGACUUGAUAUUGAUAUUGAGUAAAUUUCUGAUUUAACUCUAAUAGGAGAUUGUGUCAUAUCUUCAGUAUGGGGUUUAUCUCAUGAACUCAUUAAUCCUUUUAUUCAUUCAGAGUUGAACUAUAAGAAGACACCACGCUAAAAGAAAUCAGAUAGAUGCUGUCUUUAAAGCUCAGUUUACUGUUACUAAGGAAGAGAGAUUUGGUCUGGUGCUGACAGAACUACACGAUUUUACUGGAGAGUCACUCGAGCCGUUGUGGAGAUGCCGUUUCUGAGGGAAAAAAGCAUUUAGACUCUCUACAGUCGUGGCAUUAGAAAAAGGCGCUAAAAAUAGACAAUGUAACGGCCCAGGGUGCUCCGACCUUCAGUGCCCACGCCGCGGAUGGCCGAGCUCAGAAAGCCUACCUCCUCUUUAACGCCUCCUGAGGACCCGGAUUCCCAACCACCUAGUAGCAAGCGGCUCUGUCUUGAGGAGCCUGGAGGUGUCUUUAAGGCGGGCUGGCGACUGCCUCUGGUGCCUCGCUUGUCUGAGGCGGAAAAAGUCUGGGAGUUGUCCCCUAGACCCUUCAAGGGACUCCUUGUUUCAACGAAUGCUAUUUUCGAUAACUCCACAGACUCGUGUGUGGAGAAAUCAGUCAGUGGGAAGCAGAUAUGUAAUCUGAAAUGCUCAAAUCUCAAAUUCCAAAUGAGUAGCUGUUUGCAGUCUCCCCCCUCACAAAGUCCUGAUUCUGAUUUGAGGGCUUCAGGAAGGUCUGAGGCAGGCCUGCAUGACAGAGAGGCUUUCAGUGUGCACCGCAGUAAUAGCUCCAAAGCAGGGGUUAGUCAACUUCUGCCCAGCACCUCUAUACACGAUAUACAUGGAAUUAGAAAUGAGAAUCGAAAACAACAGUUUGUCCAAGGAAGAGACAAUGUUCACAAAGAAAAUCCAUUUUUAGAUGUUACCUUUUACAAGGAAACUAAAUCACCAUUUCAUGAAAUUAAGAACAGAUGUAAAGCUAACAGUGUUGUGCCAUCAAAUAAAAGAGAAAAUAACAUUUCAUCAUCUGUACUAAAAAUAUCAAAAUCUCAAAACCAGCCCAGCUUGGAAAUUGCCAAACCUAGCUAUUUUAGAGAUAGCGGCACAAUAAGUGUCCCUCAGUUUCCAAUGGACUUAAAUAGCAAAAUGUCCUCUGUCUAUUUAAAGGAAAUAGCGAAGAAAAAGAAUGACAAAAAAGAGGCAUAUGUUAGGGAUUUCACAAACAUUUACUGGUCCCAAAAUAGACCUGAUGUUAAGAAGCAAAAGUUACAGAAUGAUAAAAAAACUGUAGAAGCGGAAAACAUUUUUUCCAAAUGUUAUGAAAAUGACUACCCAUCACUCAGUAGCCAAAAUACUUGUAAGAGAAAAGACUUGAUCAGUUCAAACUACUGUAACUGCAGUAGUAUCCAGUGUAAUGUAAGAGACUCUAGAAAGAAUUUCGCUAUACUAGAAAAUGCAAAUUGGGAGGAAGCAGAAUGUCUGGACAGUUACGUACUUACCAGGCUGGAAAAAUCUCAAAACUGGGACUGUAACGUUAGACAUAUUUUGAGAAGAAAUAGAGGAAAUUGUUGGAUUAUAAAUAAUUGCAAGACUAAAUGUGAAAAUAUGAAAAAAACUGAAGAAAAAUGGAAUUGGCUAUUAUUAUUAGAAAUAGACCUUUUAAGCAAGGAAGAUUACCACUGUGCAAAAGUCAUCAAUGCAUAUGAAGAACAAUCAAAGCUUCUCGUAAGAGAAAUAUUAGGUAGUCAGACAGCUUUAAUAACGACUGUUUGGCUAAAUGGUAAAGGAGAAAAUGAUAAUACUCUACAGUUGAGAUACAAUACUACACAAAAAGUCUUUCAUGUGAACAACCCUUUUGAAAGUUUCAUUAUAGAAAUUUUUUAUUUCCAUAAAAGUAUUUCAGGAAAUAAAAAAGAUAAUAGUAUUUUAACCUGCUGUAACAUUUUGAAGUGUAAAAAGCAAAUUGGUAUAAUUGGUAUUCAAAAUCUAAUAACCAGAAACAUGAAUACAAAUAUAAAGAAUGGAAUUUUAAGCAUAUAUUUACAAGAUAGUGUUUCAGAACCUUUAGAUAUUCUAUUGAAAACUAACAUAGCUUUUUUGCUCAAUAACUUUGACUCUUUAACAAGAAUUGAAAAUGAUUUUGAAUUAGAAGAGGAAUGCAUUUUCAAGUGCAUGCUUUAUUUGAAGUAUCCAAAAAAUAUAGUGGAAAAUCAUACUGCAUAUCUAGUAAAGAUUUUAACUUCUUCAAGACUAUUAGAAGAUAAUAUGAAACCUAUGUUAAAGAAAAGGAAGUUAUUUAGAACUGAACAAGUUUUUGAAAAGUCUAAGAAAAAACUCAUUAAUUCCUUCAGUAUGACAACUCAAAAUACAGGUUUUCCGAUUUUUGAAACAUAUGAAAAAAUUCCCCUUUUAAUGGACUUUGAUGACAUGGAUGAAAUUUCUUUAAUAAGAGAAAUUACUUGUCAGAAUAUGAGUUGUCCUCAACAAGUUGUGAAUGUGGAAAAUUGGGCUCACUAUAAUUCUAGUACUGUUAAAGCACAUGGUAAUUCUUGUCCUCAAUUUAUACAGAACAACCGAGGAUACAUUAAUGAAAAUUUUUAUGAAGUAAAUAUGCACAGCCAAGAUUUAAAUAUGGAAAGAAAACAGGGACAUAAUAAGAUCAGUAACUUUGACUGUGAGCACAUAUUUGAAGAUCUCUGCAAUGUUAGGCAACAGGCCAUACCAGCAAGCCACAACAUAAUACAUAAUGAAGAGACCCAUACCACUUCUAUAACUCAAGUACUAAAUUUUUGGAACUUGCUAAGUGAAAUAGAAGAAAAAAAAUAUGACUUAAUUUUGAAAGAGGAAGUAAAAGUCACAGCUGAAAGUUUAACAAAUAGUUGCCAAGUUCACAAAGAUACUAAGAUAGAAAAGGAAGAGAAAGAUAGUUUUUUUCCAAUGGAUGACAUGUUUUCUGUACAGUCAGUUUCAUUAAUAAGUAAGGAAGUAAAUGUGGAAGAAAAUAAAUAUGUUAAUCAAAAUUAUGUAACAAAUACAAAUGAAUAUGAGAGUAUUUUGCCAGAAAGGGAGAUAGCUAAUUCAAAGGAUUUUCACAGAAAGAAUGACUCUGCAUUAUAUAUUAAUCAUCAAUUUGAAACUGGUCUGAGUGAAGGGAAUGAUGAAUGUUUUCAGGACUUAGCUGCUAAAUAUUUAUCAACAGAAGCUCUGACAAUAGUAAAAGAUUUUGAGAUGAAGAGAAAAUUUGACUUAGUACUUGAAGAACUUCGUAUGUUUCAUGAAAUUAGUAGGGAAAAUGAACUUCUAAGCACUGUGGAAACAAACAAUGGGCAAGAAAAUUACUUUGGAGAAAAUGAUGCUGAGAAGGUAAAAAUGGAGAUAGAAAAAGAUUUGAAAAUGGUUGUGGUCAACAAAAUACGUGCAUCUUCCUCGUUCCAUGAUACUAUAGCAGGUCCUAAUAUGGGCAAAAGUCACCAAAGUUUAUUUAAAUGGAAAACUGUACCCAAUAAUGGAGAACAGGAAGUUCCUAAUGAGAGUUGUUAUCCAAGUAGAUCAGAGGAAGAAUUACUUUACUCUACUUCUGAGAAAGAUUGUGAAACACCUUUACCUAAAAGACCUGCUUUUCUCCCUGAUGAAUGUAAAGAAGAAUUUAAUUAUUUAUUGAGAGGAGGUAGUCACUUUCCACAUGGCAUUUCAAGAGUACGACCGCUUAAGACAUGCAGUAGGCCAAUCAGGAUUGGUUUGUCAAGAAAAGCAAGGAUUAAACAACUUCAUCCUUAUCUGAAACAAAUGUGUUACGGAAACUUAAAAGAAAAUUUUUGACUUUCAUAUUUCAAAACAUUUUACAACAUCUAGAAAUGUUUUGUUUUCUUUGGAUAUAUGUUCUUCCAGCUUGGGGGUUUGGGGCUUGCUUUAUUAUAAAGUGGAGAAGUUUUUUUUUUUGAGUGUAUAAAUUAUGGUAUUACCUUUCAAAGUUAUAAAAUAUUUUAUGGAUUUUUAUAUGAUAUAAAAAUGUACACAUUAAAGCCGUUUCAUUAUUGGAUAAAA